AGACCACAGCAGAGCUCACAGAACCUGCGGGAGCCAGGCUGACCCGCCAGCAUGGUAGAGUUCGCGCCCUUGUUUAUGCCGUGGGAGCGCAGGCUGCAGACACUUGCUGUCCUACAGUUUGUCUUCUCCUUCUUGGCACUGGCCGAGAUCUGCACUGUGGGCUUCAUAGCCCUCCUGUUUACAAGAUUCUGGCUCCUCACUGUCCUGUAUGCGGCCUGGUGGUAUCUGGACCGAGACAAGCCACGGCAGGGGGGCCGGCACAUCCAGGCCAUCAGGUGCUGGACUAUAUGGAAGUACAUGAAGGACUAUUUCCCCAUCUCGCUGGUCAAGACUGCUGAGCUGGACCCCUCUCGGAACUACAUUGCGGGCUUCCACCCCCAUGGAGUCCUGGCAGUCGGAGCCUUUGCCAACCUGUGCACUGAGAGCACAGGCUUCUCUUCGAUCUUCCCCGGUAUCCGCCCCCAUCUGAUGAUGCUGACCUUGUGGUUCCGGGCCCCCUUCUUCAGAGAUUACAUCAUGUCUGCAGGGUUGGUCACAUCAGAAAAGGAGAGUGCUGCUCACAUUCUGAACAGGAAGGGUGGCGGAAACUUGCUGGGCAUCAUUGUAGGGGGUGCCCAGGAGGCCCUGGAUGCCAGGCCUGGAUCCUUCACGCUGUUACUGCGGAACCGAAAGGGCUUCGUCAGGCUCGCCCUGACACACGGGGCACCCCUGGUGCCAAUCUUCUCCUUCGGGGAGAAUGACCUAUUUGACCAGAUUCCCAACUCUUCUGGCUCCUGGUUACGCUAUAUCCAGAAUCGGUUGCAGAAGAUCAUGGGCAUCUCCCUCCCACUCUUUCAUGGCCGUGGUGUCUUCCAGUACAGCUUUGGUUUAAUACCCUACCGCCGGCCCAUCACCACUGUGGUGGGGAAGCCCAUCGAGGUACAGAAGACGCUGCAUCCCUCGGAGGAGGAGGUGAACCAGCUGCACCAGCGUUAUAUCAAAGAGCUGUGCAACCUCUUCGAGGCCCACAAACUUAAGUUCAACAUCCCUGCUGACCAGCACUUGGAGUUCUGCUGAGCCCAAAGGGCAGGGCCAACAUUAGGGAGCCCAGCAGGAGGUGCUGUGCUGAGAAGACUUCCUGGAGGUGUUUGUUGAACAUAUCUGCAGAGCCUUCCCAGACUCCUGCAAAUCCAACCCAUAUCAGGCUGUAAGUCAGAGCAGGCAAUGCAGAAGAGGAGACCAGACCAAGGGGUCAGCUGGGGCUAGGACAGUGAGGGCUGCUAGAGGGGCUGGGCCUCUCUUUGCACAUGGACACUGGGCCCCUCUCUAUAUUGAGUGGUCUGUUAACAUUCAUUGGUGGCUGAUUCCAAAAGAUGAGAGCCAAAGCUGCACGGACUCGAGUCCUAGGCUGCACACCUCACAAGCAUCUCUUCUACUGCAUUCUGUUGGUCGAAGCAAGUCACAACCCAGCAGAUUCAAGGAGUAAGGAAUAGGAUCCCCCUCUGGAUGGGAGGAGCAGCAAUGUCAUAUUACAAAAGGGUGUGGACACAUGCAGGGAUUCUUACUGCCGUCUUUGCAAACAAUCCACCAAAACUUAAAAACUAAAAGCCUGAAGCACAAGCACUCUCCACCCCAGGCACACACACCCUGGAAUUCCCUGUGUGACCAUGGUACCACCACUGUGUGUCCCGAGGAUCCCAGCUCAGCUUUGCAUCGCUGCCCUAUCUCCCUCUCGCUCUCCCCUGUUGAUCCCUCAUGCACAGCCACAGCGAGCUGUCUAAAACACAAAGCUGACCGCGCCAUUUCCUACUCAGCAUCCUUCCAUGACCCUCCAUUGCUCCUAGGAUAGGGUUUGGACCAGUCUGAAUCCAGAGGAUCAGGAUCCAGCAGGAACCAGAGGAUAAUUUGAGGAGGGUUUAAAAAGGAACCAUUUUUUGAGGUGUGUGCACUGUUUCCACCCUGAGGCCUGGAAGGAUGAAUGGAAGCAGCAGUUCCUGAACCAGGAAGACUCAUGUGUGGGGGCCAUUGCUGGUCAAGGGGCACGAACAGGUCUGGUGACCCUGCAAGGGAGGAGCCAGGAGCAAGCAUUCCCACUUCACCUUCCUCCAUUCAGUCUGCUGCCAAGUUCCCCACUGCCUGAGCCCAACUAGAAGCUGGAGGGAAGGAGGGCCUGUGGCUGCAGUCCAGGCAUGUAGGCCUCCUGGGAAAGGGAGAAUGGCAAAGACAGGCAGAGUGGAUCUGGAGGGGUCAACGGAAGACGGAACAUGUCCACUUCCAGGCCCGAGCUUCUCAGCCUGCCGUUUGCCACUCUCCAGCAUCUGGCCCAGCCUGUCCAUCCUCAUCUCUCUUCCUCCCUUACUCCGUGCUCCCAUCACUCGGAACCAUUUGCAUUUCUUUGUCUCAGCUAUAUUGUCUCACCUCUGAGUUUUUGCCCAUGAUGUUGGAUGCCAUGGAAUGCCAUAUCCUCCCCAUUAUCUCCCCCUUGUCUGGAUAAUUCCUACUCAUCCUACAAUACUGAUUUUAUCUGUGCAAAGAAGUCUUCCCCAGUGCCUCUGGUUGACAGGGGUUUCCUCUGGCUUCUCCAGACUUUCUGUUCCUCCACCACAGCCCUUAGCACCCUGGGGAGGAGGUGUUGCUGUCCAGGUAAAUGCUGCGCCAAUGCCCCUGCCUCUAGUGCACUCCCUCCAGCCUACCCACAAACAGGACCUGCAUCCUGUCUCACAAAUAAAACUGAACUCUUGAAA